GCGGCGAGGCUCCCGCGCGCGGCUGAGUGCGGACUGGAGUGGGAACCCGGGUCCCCGCGCUUAGAGAACACGCGAUGACCACGUGGAGCCUCCGGCGGAGGCCGGCCCGCACGCUGGGACUCCUGCUGCUGGUCGUCUUGGGCUUCCUGGUGCUCCGCAGGCUGGACUGGAGCACCCUGGUCCCUCUGCGGCUCCGCCAUCGACAGCUGGGGCUGCAGGCCAAGGGCUGGAACUUCAUGCUGGAGGAUUCCACCUUCUGGAUCUUCGGGGGCUCCAUCCACUAUUUCCGUGUGCCCAGGGAGUACUGGAGGGACCGCCUGCUGAAGAUGAAGGCCUGUGGCUUGAACACCCUCACCACCUAUGUUCCGUGGAACCUGCAUGAGCCAGAAAGAGGCAAAUUUGACUUCUCUGGGAACCUGGACCUGGAGGCCUUCGUCCUGAUGGCCGCAGAGAUCGGGCUGUGGGUGAUUCUGCGUCCAGGCCCCUACAUCUGCAGUGAGAUGGACCUCGGGGGCUUGCCCAGCUGGCUACUCCAAGACCCUGGCAUGAGGCUGAGGACAACUUACAAGGGCUUCACCGAAGCAGUGGACCUUUAUUUUGACCACCUGAUGUCCAGGGUGGUGCCACUCCAGUACAAGCGUGGGGGACCUAUCAUUGCCGUGCAGGUGGAGAAUGAAUAUGGUUCCUAUAAUAAAGACCCCGCAUACAUGCCCUACGUCAAGAAGGCACUGGAGGACCGUGGCAUUGUGGAACUGCUCCUGACUUCAGACAACAAGGAUGGGCUGAGCAAGGGGAUUGUCCAGGGAGAUCCCCAGCCUGGGGGGCUUUGCUCUUCUUCCAGAGAGCUACAUGGCUGUUCUCCGAAGUUAGCGAGGCUUUCUGUAGCACCACACUUGAAAUUGAACUUCUUCCUUCGUGGGGCUCACUCAAUCCUUCUCCCUGCUUUCUUUUCGCCCUCUCACCUUCCAGUCUUGGCCACCAUCAACUUGCAGUCAACACACGAGCUGCAGCUACUGACCACCUUUCUCUUCAACGUCCAGGGGACUCAGCCCAAGAUGGUGAUGGAGUACUGGACGGGGUGGUUUGACUCGUGGGGAGGCCCUCACAAUAUCUUGGAUUCUUCUGAGGUUUUGAAAACCGUGUCUGCCAUUGUGGACGCCGGCUCCUCCAUCAACCUCUACAUGUUCCACGGAGGCACCAACUUUGGCUUCAUGAAUGGAGCCAUGCACUUCCAUGACUACAAGUCAGAUGUCACCAGCUAUGACUAUGAUGCUGUGCUGACAGAAGCCGGCGAUUACACGGCCAAGUACAUGAAGCUUCGAGACUUCUUCGGCUCCAUCUCAGGCAUCCCUCUCCCUCCCCCACCUGACCUUCUUCCCAAGAUGCCGUAUGAGCCCUUAACGCCAGUCUUGUACCUGUCUCUGUGGGACGCCCUCAAGUACCUGGGGGAGCCAAUCAAGUCUGAAAAGCCCAUCAACAUGGAGAACCUGCCAGUCAAUGGGGGAAAUGGACAGUCCUUCGGGUACAUUCUCUAUGAGACCAGCAUCACCUCGUCUGGCAUCCUCAGUGGCCACGUGCAUGAUCGGGGGCAGGUGUUUGUGAACACAGUAUCCAUAGGAUUCUUGGACUACAAGACAACGAAGAUUGCUGUCCCCCUGAUCCAGGGUUACACCGUGCUGAGGAUCUUGGUGGAGAAUCGUGGGCGAGUCAACUAUGGGGAGAAUAUUGAUGACCAGCGCAAAGGCUUAAUUGGAAAUCUCUAUCUGAAUGAUUCACCCCUGAAAAACUUCAGAAUCUAUAGCCUGGAUAUGAAGAAGAGCUUCUUUCAGAGGUUCGGCCUGGACAAAUGGAGUUCCCUCCCAGAAACACCCACAUUACCUGCUUUCUUCUUGGGUAGCUUGUCCAUCAGCUCCACCCCUUGUGACACCUUUCUGAAGCUGGAGGGCUGGGAGAAGGGGGUUGUAUUCAUCAAUGGCCAGAACCUUGGACGUUACUGGAACAUUGGACCCCAGAAGACGCUUUACCUCCCAGGUCCCUGGUUGAGCAGCGGAAUCAACCAGGUCAUCGUUUUUGAGGAGACGAUGGCGGGCCCUGCAUUACAGUUCACGGAAACCCCCCACCUGGGCAGGAACCAGUACAUUAAGUGAGCGGUGGCACCCCCUCCUGCUGGUGCCAGUGGGAGACUGCCGCCUCCUCUUGACCUGAAGCCUGGUGGCUGCUGCCCCACCCCUCACUGCAAAAGCAUCUCCUUAAGUAGCAACCUCAGGGACUGGGGGCUACAGUCUGCCCCUGUCUCAGCUCAAAACCCUAAGCCUGCAGGGAAAGGUGGGAUGGCUCUGGGCCUGGCUUUGUUGAUGAUGGCUUUCCUACAGCCCUGCUCUUGUGCCGAGGCUGUCGGGCUGUCUCUAGGGUGGGAGCAGCUAAUCAGAUCGCCCAGCCUUUGGCCCUCAGAAAAAGUGCUGAAACGUGCCCUUGCACUGGACGUCACAGCCCUGCGAGCAUCUGCUGGACUCAGGCGUGCUCUUUGCUGGUUCCUGGGAGGCUUGGCCACAUCCCUCAUGGCCCCAUUUUAUCCCCGAAAUCCUGGGUGUGUCACCAGUGUAGAGGGUGGGGAAGGGGUGUCUCACCUGAGCUGACUUUGUUCUUCCUUCACAACCUUCUGAGCCUUCUUUGGGAUUCUGGAAGGAACUCGGCGUGAGAAACAUGUGACUUCCCCUUUCCCUUCCCACUCGCUGCUUCCCACAGGGUGACAGGCUGGGCUGGAGAAACAGAAAUCCUCACCCUGCGUCUUCCCAAGUUAGCAGGUGUCUCUGGUGUUCAGUGAGGAGGACAUGUGAGUCCUGGCAGAAGCCAUGGCCCAUGUCUGCACAUCCAGGGAGGAGGACAGAAGGCCCAGCUCACAUGUGAGUCCUGGCAGAAGCCAUGGCCCAUGUCUGCACAUCCAGGGAGGAGGACAGAAGGCCCAGCUCACAUGUGAGUCCUGGCAGAAGCCAUGGCCCAUGUCUGCACAUCCAGGGAGGAGGACAGAAGGCCCAGCUCACAUGUGAGUCCUGGCAGAAGCCAUGGCCCAUGUCUGCACAUCCAGGGAGGAGGACAGAAGGCCCAGCUCACAUGUGAGUCCUGGCAGAAGCCAUGGCCCAUGUCUGCACAUCCAGGGAGGAGGACAGAAGGCCCAGCUCACAUGUGAGUCCUGGCAGAAGCCAUGGCCCAUGUCUGCACAUCCAGGGAGGAGGACAGAAGGCCCAGCUCAGUGGCCCCCGCCCCCCACCCCCCACGCCCGAACAGCAGGGGCAGAGCAGCCCUCCUUCGAAGUGUGUCCAAGUCCGCAUUUGAGCCUUGUUCUGGGGCCCAGCCCAACACCUGGCUUGGGCUCACUGUCCUGAGUUGCAGUAAAGCUAUAACCUUGAAUCACA